CUGGACCCGUUUUUAUGAAGAAUUUUCUGACAUAAGCACUUCUCCAGAUUCCUGAAGGCCUCCUUACCUUCACAGAUGCGCCUCUCAGAACAAAAUAGAAAAUACUCACCAGACUCUUUUCUGCUCCCAGGAUGGUGGGCUCAGUGUGAAGGUUAUAACAGCCAGUAUAUCUGUGAGAGGGAGACAGCCAGGCCCUGAGAUAAAGGUUUGUGAUUCUGCGACCUCACCUCCCCGAAGAACCACAGUUAUUAGUUUACCUUUAGCAAAAUUGCAGUGCAUGCUAGGAAAGUCAAAAAUAUUUUUUCUAAUAAUUUGUUUCCAUUCUCAAUUACCAGAAACAAUUACAGUGUCUAGUGAGCAUCUCCAAAGAGACUAAUGCAGUAUUUAGAAGAGGCUUUUUUAUUUCCAUGGACCCUGGAAGCAGACAGGGGCUCAGGUGGAGAGUGCAGGACACGCUGAGGUCUGAGCCAUGAGGGACUCUCAGCAAAUUGUACACCUCACGCGACCUUCUGCUUCCUUGAGUUCUGCUCAAAAUCUAACUUUUUCCUGACUCUGAGAACCAUAUGCUUCCAGACCCCUUCUAGAUUAUGGGAAGGCAAAUGGGAUACCAUGAAGAGACCAAGAAGGAUCUAUUAAUGCACUAAGAGUGAAAUGAAGAAUGUGAUGUCAAUAAUUGAUAGUCUGAAACAUUAAAUGGCACUUUCUGAUAUACAUGAAUGAUUAAAUAAAUAAUUGGGAGAUAAGAGACCCAACUCCUAUGCAGAAAAAUUCCAAAUAACUCUUGUAGACACUCCACCUCCAAGGAGGUGGAAUACACAUAACUCCCAACUCCACAAAUGCAGGCUGCACAGUGCUGCUUCCUUUUAAACAAUACAAUAUGGCAGGGAGAGAAUGUGAGGAUUUUUAUAGCUGAGAAACCUGACAGACACAGCCUCAGACAGGUGAUCAAGGUUGACAUCCAAAGGGGAUUAAGUAAUGUUAAUAGUAUACACCUUUGAUAGGAUGUGAUAAAAAUGGCACUUCUCAUUGGUUUUUCUCCCCAGUAUACUUAACCUUUGUCUAAUCAUGGAAAACAUCAGACAAAUCCCAAUAGAGUGGCAGUCCCCAAUAACACAUUGACAGCCCUGCUACCUAACCAGUACUCCUCAAAGCUGACCAGGUUAUAAAAAACAAGAGUCUGAGAAUCUGUUAGAGCCAAGGGGAGCCUAAAGACACAUAAUGGUUAAAUCUAAUGUGGUGGCCUGGACAGGAUCCUGGCAGAGAAAAGGUCAGGGAGCCGAAGGCCUGUGGGACGUGACCAACUCAGCAUUCCUCUGGAGGCUAUAUGAUCAAACAGCAAACUGUUUAUCAAGAAUGCAGGAUAUGGGCAAACUCACACUUCCCUGCCACCAAAAGGUUUGCUGAGGGACAUGUCUCCCUUGCACCGGGCUCCUUGAAGUUAUCUAAUGAGAAAUCUAGCACCUAUUAUUCAAAGGAUGCAGUCUUGCAAGCCUGCUGUGAACCAAACGGCUGACUGACAAUUACCUGACAAUCACCCUGCCUUUCUCGCUCUCUCUUUUGCCUAAUAAAUAUGGAGGGCUGUGUAAAGCUCAGAGCCCUUGUCCACUAGAGGCAAAUAUACUCUCUUGUCUUUUAUUUCCACAUUUGCCCCCUUUGUUCAAUCCCCCUAGGUCCAUGUGGGUUACAAGUGGCGCCUGAACAGGGACAGAAUUGGGUGCUUUAUAAGUGGCAUCACGAAGUGGCACCCUGAACAGCGACAGUGGCAUCCAAACUCGGGACUAUGAGGACAUAAACGAAGAAGGUCUGCUGGAGCAGAGGAACUGAAAUUGACAAGGUGAACAAGGACCCCGGGACGAGUCUGCCGGCAGCGGAUAUAAGACACAGGAGUGUUGCCAUGUUGUCCAAACUGGUCUCGAAAUUCUGGAGUCAAGCAGUCUGCCUGCCUCGUUCUCCAAACGUGCUGGGAUUACAGGCAUGAGCCACUACGCCUGGCCAAGUAUUCGGUAUUUAUAAAAUCUACAGUAGUACACAGUUAUGUCGUAGGCCAUCACAUUCGGUCACCACACACUCACUGACUCAUCCAGAGCAAUUUCUAGUCCUGCAAGCGCCAUUCAUGGAUUGACUUAUAAACAGUCAUGCUAUGUGAUGAAGAAGCCCAGAAGAGGAAAGCAAAGGAGUCAGGGAUGGCUCUUCCUCAGGGACGCUUGACAUUCAUGGACGUGGCCAUCGAAUUCUCUCAGGAGGAGUGGAAAUCCCUGGACCCUGGACAGAGGGCUUUAUACAGGGACGUGAUGUUGGAGAACUACAGGAACCUGGUCUUUCUGGGAAUCUGUCUUCCUGACCUAAGUAUUAUUUCCAUGUUGAAGCAAAGGAGAGAGCCCUUGAUUCUGCAAAGUCAAGUUAAAAUAGUAAAAAAUACAGAUGGAAGGGAAUGUGUCAGAAGCGUGAACACAGGGAGGAGCUGUGUAUUGGGAAGCAAUGCAGAAAACAAGCCUAUUAAAAAUCAACUUGGAUUAACCCUUGAGGCACAUCUGUCUGAAUUGCAGCUGUUUCAAGCCGGAAGGAAAAUUUACAGAAGUAAUCAAGUUGAAAAGUUUACAAACCAUCGUUCCUCAGUUUCACCACUUCAAAAAAUUUCUUCUAGUUUCACAACACACAUUUUUAAUAAAUAUAGAAAUGAUCUUAUUGAUUUCCCAUUACUCCCACAAGAAGAGAAAGCAUACAUUAGAGGAAAAUCUUAUGAAUAUGAAUGUAGUGAAGAUGGUGAAGUUUUUAGAGUCCGUGCAAGCCUUACUAACCAUCAAGUAAUCCAUACUGCAGAGAAACCUUACAAAUGUACUGAAUGUGGCAAGGUCUUCAGUCGCAAUUCACACCUUGUAGAACAUUGGAGAAUUCAUACUGGACAGAAGCCUUACAAAUGUAGUGAAUGUGACAAGGUGUUUAAUCGCAAUUCAAACCUUGCACGACAUCAAAGAAUUCAUACUGGAGAGAAGCCUCACAAAUGUAACGAAUGUGGCAAAGCUUUUAGAGAGUGUUCGGGACUUACUACCCAUCUUGUAAUCCAUACUGGAGAGAAACCUUACAAAUGUAAUGAGUGUGGCAAGAACUUCAGGCACAAAUUUUCUCUAACCAAUCAUCAGAGAAGUCACACGGCGGAAAAACCUUACAAAUGUAAUGAAUGUGGCAAGGUCUUUAGUCUGCUUUCAUACCUUGCACGGCAUCAAAUAAUUCAUAGUACAGAGAAGCCCUACAAAUGUAACGAAUGUGGAAGAGCAUUUCACAAGCGUCCGGGCCUUAUGGCCCAUCUUCUAAUCCAUACUGGAGAGAAACCUUACAAAUGUAAUGAAUGUGACAAAGUCUUUGGGCGCAAAUUAUACCUAACCAACCAUCAGAGAAUUCAUACUGGAGAGAGACCUUACAAGUGUAAUGCAUGUGGCAAGGUCUUCAAUCAAAAUCCACACCUUUCACGACAUCGGAAAAUUCAUGCUGGAGAGAAUUCACUGCGUACCUUACAGAUGGAAUGAAUGUGGCAAAAUCUUUAGUUAGAAUUCACACCUAGCACAACAUUGGAGGACUCAGGAGAAAAACCUUACAAAUAUCAUAAAUGUGGCAAAGAAUUUAGUUUGCAUUGAAGCCUCAUCACUCAUCUCUUGAUCCACACUGAAAGGAAACCCUACAAAUGUAAAGUUAAUAACAUAUAUAAAUAAUCUAUAAAGAGAGAACAGUUAUAUCAGAAUAGAGCAUUUAAUGAAAACUACCAGUAUAGCAUAUUCUUGAGUAGGAUUCACAUUUAACUGCUGGCACCGUAAUUUGUAACUCUUUGAUUUAGAAUGUACAUACUUCUCAUGUUUUAAGUAAUAAAGUUUAAAGUUUUUUUUUAGUUUUUUCUUUUUUUUUUGAGACGAAGUCUCGCUGUAUUACCCAGGCUGGAGUGCAGUGGCAUGAUCUUGGCUCACUGCAACCUCCGUCUCCCGGAUUCAAGCAAUUCUCCUGCCUCAGCCUCCUGAGUAGCUGGGAUUACAGGCAUGUGCCACUACUGCCCGGCUAAUUUUUGUAUUUUUAGUCGAGACGGGGUUUCCCUCCGUUGGCCAGGCCGGUUUCAAACUCCUGACCUCAAGUGAUCCACUGGCCUUGGCCUCCCAAAGUGCUGGGAUUAUAGGUGUGAGCCACAGCGCCCGGCCUAGUUUAAAUUUUUCUUAGUGUGAAUGAAUUACAUCCUUUCUACCAGCGUUGUUUAAUCUUACCUCAGGAGGAUACUUUAUAGUAGAGAAUAAUAACCCAUUAUGAUUUUAAGGUUGAAGCAGCCAGAAAAGUGUGUGUGUGUGUAUGUGUGUGAGACAUAAAACAACAUACGCUUCUGGGUGCAAUAUACUUAAGUAAGUAUGAUGUUGAGUAAUUACACUUAGUACUUGAGUUAGUUUCUCUGUACUCUGGUGUAGGAUGUUUAUGUGGGUAAAGUCAAAAUCACUUUAAUAGUACAAUUUCAGCCUUGUACACCCUCAAAUGUGUGUGAGUGUUAAAGAGUAUGCCCUGUA